AUAUAGAGAUUUGAGUAAAUCACAUUCCCUUUGUAAAUGCUCUAUGUUCCCAUGAAACACAGCCACGAUAUUAUCUCCCUUCUUGGCCCCCUCCAUCUCCCUUCCCCUUGAGACAUUCUUCUACUUUCUAUUUGUUGGCACCUGGCCAAACCCUAGCCAAAAGAUUCAAUUUCUGUGUAGGAAACAGAAGCUAUUGGUACCCAGGUUCUGUUUCACCAGAAAGGCUCAGUCUCCACACCCGCUGAUUUCAUGCCCACGUUGAUCAGUUUUCAUCUCGUUAUGCCAGGCAUGUCCAAACCUAACAGAGGCUUCAGUUAGCUGGGAUACCCCUGAGAUUGCUAUGCAAAGAUUGUUCUCCUGAGAGCAAAUGCCAGAUCCUGCCAGAGUCUUACUAGCUAGGUUAACACAAACUUUUUAUGAAAUAAUAGUCACCCUGAACAGCUACUUUCCCCUAAAUUAAAAAGGCUACAAAAUUUUUGUCUUACCCCAAAUUUAAUGUAUAAAAAUUACCUGAACUCUAGAGAUGAAAAAUGUAAACAUAGCACCCUCUAUACUAGGAAUCUUAACCAUUUAUUGAUGUCACACACAUAUUCUCUCCCAUAUUUGUAGAUUUGUUAAAGAGAAUUCACAGGCCUCCUUAUAUUUGAAUACAACUGUCUCAAGAACUCUUAAAAAUGUACUUCUUGAAGUAUUCUUGGACCUGGCAUGAAACAAUAAAGCUGUGAAUGAACACAUAAUUCAUUUACCUACAGCUACUUCUUAGUCUAUUUUGGGAAGUCCUACUCUGCCACUGAAGUGGUGCUUUCUCCCACUCAGGAAGAGGAACUGUCAGCACUCUCAUUCAGAACUUGCCUUCUACUUAGCACGGAUGGCGGAAAGUACAAAAACGCUGGGCAUGAGAUGCUGUUAAAAAUCCUUCUGUGCUCACAGGGGAGGCAUUCCAAAGCCAGCCCUCAUGGAUAGAAGUAAAACUCCAUCCUCAAGUCAAGCUGGACUUCUGAAUGUCGAGUUAAAAUGAAAUUAUCAUGGUAACACAUUACCUGGGCUUCCAAUCAGGGAGCGAUUGAAGGCUCCUUGGUGGCUAAGGUAUGGCUCAGAGCCAAGUGUGGUGUUCCAGGGUACCAAGUCCUCUGCUCAAUAGCUUUCAUUCUGAGUGGCACCAACACAUUUAUAAUGGAGAGUCUCUCCUAACUUUUAUCAUCACCAGGAAGUGUGUUCAUCAAGGUGUUAUCUAUUCUACUAGCCUUGAUGCUCACUGUUCUAGUUAAAAGGCUAUCCAAAAAUACUAUGUCUUGGGGUACUACUGAGAUUUGUUGAAACAUUGGAUAAUUGUUCCCCUUCCCCCUCACCCAACCCAUCAUGUUGACAGUAAAGUCCCUUAUCCUUGAGGCAGCUGACAUUUCAGAGGGGCUCAAGGGUGCUUAGCUUGAAAACAAGAACAAAAUAUGUCUGAUCACGCCCGUGUCAACUGUGGUUAAGUGUGGGAACCAGGAUAAGGACAACUGAAGGCAUGGAUUGAGUUGUAAGGGGCCGCCUCCUUUUCCCUAGGCCCAGUUAUUGUCAACAUGAGGGUUUGUUCUAGAGCUACUGUCUUAUCUGCCACAUUCCUUUUUCAUAAGAAGGCAAUUUGGUAGCAUCAGAAUUUAUCAUUGUUUUUGUCCAAAAAUGUGUGUCCCAGGCCAGGCGCUGUGGCUCAUGCCUGUAAUCCUAGCACUUUGGGAGGCCGAGGUGGGUGGAUCACCUGAGGUCAGGAGUUUGAGACCAGCCUCACCAAUAUGAUGAAACCCCGUCUCUACUAAAAAUACAAAAAAUUAGCCAGGUGUGGUGGCGUGCACCUGUAGUCCCAGCUACUUGGGAGGCUGAGGCGGGAGAAUUGCUUGAACCUGGGAUGCAGAGGUUGCAGUGAGCUGAGAUAGCGCCACUGCACUCCAGCCUAGGUGACAGAGUGAGACUCUGUCUCAAAAAAUAAAAAAUAAAAAAUAAAUGUGUGUCCCUCCAGUGCCGCUUGCCCCUUGUUCUCCCAAGCACCAGGGGGACCCCUGGUCUUAGAUUCAAGUUGCAUCACUAGACUAACCAGCUCUGGGAACCAGAGGGACACUGGAGGAACUAGUUUGGGAAAUGAAAAACAUCUGCAAUGAGAGUAUUACUAGAACAUUUGCAUCGGGAAAAACAGAAAAGGUGAUCUUUCAAGCACUCAAGGAGUUAGGUCUUCCCAGUGGAAAGAAUGAUGAAAUUGAGCCCACAGCAUUUUCUUAUGAAAAGUUCUAUGAACUGACACAAAAGAUUUGUCCUCGGACAGAUAUAGAAGAUCUUUUCAAAAAAAUCAAUGGAGACAAAACUGAUUAUUUAACGGUAGACCAAUUAGUGAGCUUUCUAAAUGAACAUCAACGAGAUCCUCGAUUGAAUGAAAUUUUAUUUCCAUUUUAUGAUGCCAAAAGGGCAAUGCAGAUCAUUGAGAUGUAUGAACCUGAUGAAGAUUUGAAGAAAAAAGGCCUUAUAUCAAGUGAUGGGUUUUGCAGAUAUCUGAUGUCAGAUGAAAACGCCCCAGUCUUCCUAGAUCGUUUAGAACUUUACCAAGAAAUGGACCAUCCUCUGGCUCACUACUUCAUCAGUUCUUCCCAUAACACUUAUCUCACUGGCAGACAGUUCGGCGGGAAGUCUUCGGUAGAAAUGUACAGACAGGUUCUCCUGGCUGGUUGCAGAUGUGUUGAACUUGACUGCUGGGAUGGAAAAGGUGAAGACCAAGAACCAAUAAUAACUCAUGGAAAAGCAAUGUGUACAGAUAUCCUUUUUAAGGAUGUAAUUCAAGCCAUCAAGGAAACUGCAUUUGUCACAUCAGAAUAUCCUGUAAUUCUCUCCUUUGAAAAUCACUGCAGCAAAUAUCAACAGUACAAGAUGUCCAAAUAUUGCGAAGAUCUAUUUGGGGAUCUCCUGUUGAAACAAGCACUUGAAUCACAUCCACUUGAACCAGGCAGGGCUUUGCCAUCCCCCAAUGACCUCAAAAGAAAAAUACUCAUAAAAAACAAGCGGCUGAAACCUGAAGUUGAAAAAAAACAGCUGGAAGCUUUGAGAAGCAUGAUGGAAGCUGGAGAAUCUGCCUCCCCAGCAAACAUCUUAGAGGACGAUAAUGAAGAGGAGAUCGAAAGUGCUGACCAAGAGGAGGAAGCUCACCCCGAAUUCAAAUUUGGAAAUGAACUUUCUGCUGAUGACUUGGGUCACAAGGAAGCUGUUGCAAAUAGCGUCAAGAAGGCUUCAGAUGACCUUGAACAUGAAAACAACAAAAAGGGCCUGGUCACUGUAGAAGAUGAGCAGGCGUGGAUGGCAUCUUAUAAAUAUGUAGGUGCUACCACUAAUAUCCAUCCAUAUUUGUCCACAAUGAUCAACUACGCCCAGCCUGUAAAGUUUCAAGGUUUCCAUGUGGCAGAAGAACGCAAUAUUCAUUAUAACAUGUCUUCUUUUAAUGAAUCAGUCGGUCUUGGCUACUUGAAGACACAUGCAAUUGAAUUUGUCAAUUAUAACAAACGGCAAAUGAGUCGCAUUUACCCCAAGGGAGGCCGAGUCGAUUCCAGUAAUUACAUGCCUCAGAUUUUCUGGAACGCUGGCUGCCAGAUGGUUUCACUGAACUAUCAAACCCCAGAUUUAGCGAUGCAAUUGAAUCAGGGAAAAUUUGAGUAUAAUGGAUCGUGCGGGUACCUUCUCAAACCAGAUUUCAUGAGGCGGCCUGAUCGAACAUUUGACCCCUUCUCUGAAACUCCUGUUGAUGGUGUUAUUGCAGCCACUUGCUCAGUGCAGGUUAUAUCAGGUCAAUUCUUAUCAGAUAAGAAAAUUGGCACCUACGUAGAGGUGGAUAUGUAUGGGUUGCCCACUGACACCAUACGUAAGGAAUUCCGAACUCGCAUGGUUAUGAAUAAUGGACUCAAUCCAGUUUACAAUGAAGAGUCAUUUGUAUUUCGGAAGGUGAUCCUGCCGGACCUGGCUGUCUUGAGAAUAGCUGUGUAUGAUGAUAACAACAAGCUGAUUGGCCAGAGGAUCCUCCCGCUUGAUGGCCUCCAAGCCGGAUAUCGACACAUUUCCCUUCGAAAUGAGGGAAAUAAACCAUUAUCACUACCAACAAUUUUCUGCAAUAUUGUUCUUAAAACAUAUGUGCCUGAUGGAUUUGGAGAUAUCGUGGAUGCUUUAUCAGAUCCAAAGAAAUUUCUCUCAAUUACAGAAAAGAGAGCAGACCAAAUGAGAGCUAUGGGCAUUGAAACUAGUGACAUAGCCGACGUGCCCAGUGACACUUCCAAAAAUGACAAGAAAGGAAAGGCCAACACCGCCAAAGCAAAUGUGACCCCUCAGAGUAGCUCUGAGCUCAGACCAACCACCACGGCUGCCCUGGCCUCUGGUGUGGAAGCCAAGAAAGGUAUUGAACUUAUCCCUCAAGUAAGGAUAGAAGACUUAAAGCAGAUGAAGGCUUACUUGAAGCAUUUAAAGAAACAGCAGAAGGAGCUAAAUUCUUUAAAGAAGAAACAUGCAAAGGAACACAGUACCAUGCAGAAGUUACACUGCACGCAAGUUGACAAAAUUGUGGCACAGUAUGACAAAGAGAAGUCGACUCAUGAGAAAAUCCUAGAGAAGGCAAUGAAGAAGAAGGGGGGAAGUAAUUGUCUCGAAAUGAAAAAAGAAACAGAAAUCAAAAUUCAGACGCUGACAUCAGAUCACAAAUCUAAGGUCAAAGAGAUUGUAGCACAGCACACAAAGGAAUGGUCAGAAAUGAUCAAUACCCACAGUGCUGAGGAGCAAGAAAUCCGAGACCUGCACCUCAGCCAGCAGUGUGAGCUGCUGAAAAAGCUACUCAUCAAUGCCCACGAGCAGCAAACCCAGCAGCUGAAACUGUCCCAUGACAGGGAAAGCAAGGAAAUGCGAGCACACCAGGCUAAGAUUUCUAUGGAAAAUAGCAAAGCCAUCAGCCAAGAUAAAUCUAUCAAGAAUAAAGCAGAACGGGAAAGGCGAGUCAGGGAGUUAAACAGCAGCAACACUAAAAAGUUUCUGGAAGAAAGAAAGAGACUUGCCAUGAAGCAGUCCAAAGAAAUGGAUCAGUUGAAAAAAGUCCAGCUUGAACAUCUAGAAUUCCUAGAGAAACAGAAUGAGCAGCUUUUGAAAUCCUGUCAUGCAGUGUCCCAAACGCAAGGCGAAGGAGAUGCAGCAGAUGGUGAAAUUGGAAGCCGAGAUGGACCGCAGACCAGCAACAGUAGUAUGAAACUCCAAAAUGCAAACUGAAGCAGCAAACCCACAAAGCAUCAAAAGACUCACUCACAAACUUCUGAACACAAACUCCAUGGAUGAAAGCUGUUUAUUUUGUUUCCUUUAUGUGUAAACAAGAUGAUAUCUGAAACCAGAGAGACUUGGAAUGUCUGACUGACUUCUAUUUAACAGCUUGAGUAUUGCAUUUCCUUGGCCAAACAAAAAUAGCUACAAAUCCACAAAAAUUUACUAUUCCAGUAAGGCAGAGUCCAACCAUUGAUAAUACAACUUAAACAUGUUUGCUAUAAAAUACCAUCACAAGUAAAUGAGCUUGGUGUGAACAACUCUCCUUUGUGAUGCCUUAGGACAUGUUUGAACUGCAGCAAAAAACAAAAACAAAAAACAGUGCAUUAGCAAUUUCAUAGCAAGUGCAUGCACUAGGAAAAGAAAACUCUGUCUACAAGUUUAUUAGCAGAAGUGGUGGUCUGCUAGACAAAUAAUUUUGCAAAAUUUUUCUACAUCUAAGUUACCUCAUCAGUAAGUGCCAUGUCUCUACCAUGCCAUCAGAGGCUAAUUUCCUGUAAAAGUUGUGGAAAUUGUUAGAACAAUAGAAAAAUAGAGCAGUGUAUGUGUGCCAAAACUCAUCAUUACUCAAAGGAGAACUGUGUUAGGCACAUUUAAGAAAGUUUACAUCUGACAUUGCUUUAUAGGAAUUGUUUCUGCAGAUUCCGGAUAUUAUAAUUCACACCAUAAAGAUUGUGAAGUGGUUAUUGGCAAACGUUUGUAAAUGUGACCAUGUAUAAAGUAUUUAUACUCUUUAAUUCACACUGUUAGAGAGCAAAAUCAUCUAAGUAUUGCCACAUGACAAGAUUAGUAAACAGGAAUACUAGAACUAUGUUUGCAUGAUACACAAGCACCAAUAAAGACUAAUCCAUACACAGUUAACCUAAUGCCAAAUAAAUACUGGUUAAAUAAAUGUAUGGCACAGAAUAUAAUUUGACUAUCAAGACUUUUAGCAUAAUGAAAAACCCUCUCUCUAUAUAUAUAUGUGUAUAUGAAUUAUGUGGGCAUUCUUGAUACUUCAAGUUCUAGUUUGAAAAAAAUACAUAACUAAUUUAAUUUUACACAAAAAUAUUUAUGCAGAUUUUCAGAAUUUCAUAUCAGGAAAUGACCUUUUUAUGUCUGUUAAAUAUCAAAACAAUUUGCUACAGUGUUAAUCUGCAUGGUCUUUAAGCCUGCUGUAGUUGAGUUGCAGACAGUGCAUGAAAAAGUAUUCCGCUGGGAAUUGAGCCAUGCCACCAAAGCCAAGAGGAGCGCAUGGAAACCCGGUAGUCUAGAACUAAUCAGAUUACUGAUUUUAGGGCACAGCACCAGAUGAAUUGUUGUAUAUGCUUGUAAAAAUUGAUUCUGUGUGUUCCUCUGAACAAAGCGGAGAAAAUGAUGAUACCAUCAAUAUUGAAAUUAAACUUCCAACUUCUCUAAUAAAAAAUUAAAACACGCAUAACACUCGUCAAGAGUAUUUGCUCCCAAGACACAUUCUAGCAAAUGUUUUGCCUUUUUCAUAUACAUGAUAUCAUCGUUAUUUUCAAAGGGGGCUUAUUAAUACCCUCAGCAUGUUUUUCACCCAAAUGAUGCAAAACAUGCAGAUUCUAGUUGACUUCAGUUGUAAUAGACUUGUUUUUCUCCUAUUUAUGAUUUGAAGUGGAUUCUGUAAAAUAUCUCUUGUUCUUAGUUUCCUUAUCUGUAAAACAGUGGAGUUAGACUACAUAUCUUUUGGCACUAACAUCUCAUGAAAAAUUAUGGUUAAUAAAAUAUCACCACAUUUGGAUUGCCAA